AGACCAGAGCCUUGGCUCAAAGGCAAACAAAAGGAAAUGCCCGGCUCCCCAUGGCUGUGGCCAGCACCUUCAUACCAGGGCUCAACCCUCAGAACCCUCAUUAUAUCCCAGGGGUAACAGCAGAGGAAGGAUCGAAAGCCCAGGCAGAGAACUUAGAAAUGCCUGCUCCAAAUAUAUACACUGCUGAGUCCAGAAAGAUCAGGGCUUCAGAGGUCUCCGCUUCUGCCUCUGGGGAUGGCGGGGCAGGGCGAUUCUGGUGAGUGGGAGAGUCUGUGCUGCAGGUACACUGGACACUGCCCACUACUUCGGUUCAGCGUGGGCCAGACCUAUGGGCAGGUGACUGGUCAGCUACUUCGAGGCCCUCCUGGCCUAGCCUGGCCCCCUGUCCACCGCACACUUCUGCCUCCCAUUCGGCCUCCAAGAUCUCCUGAGGUUCCCAGGGAGAGUCUACCUGUCAGGCGUGGGCAAGAAAGGCUCAGCUCCAGCAUGAUCCCUGGGUACACAGGUUUUGUACCCCGGGCACAGUUCAUCUUUGCCAAGAACUGCAGCCAGGUCUGGGCCGAGGCUCUGAGUGACUUUACUCACUUGCAUGAAAAGCAAGGGAGUGAAGAGCUACCAAAGGAGGCCAAGGGAAGAAAGGACACAGAGAAGGACCAGGUGCCAGAGCCGGAGGGGCAGCUGGAGGAGCCGACACUGGAGGUGGUGGAACAAGCUUCUCCCUACUCCAUGGAUGACAGGGACCCUCGGAAGUUCUUCAUGUCAGCUUUCCUGUGCUCACCAACCAGGCACUGCAGGAAUUUGGGCAGAAGCACUCACCAGGCAGUGCCCAGGACCCCAAACAUCUCCCCCCACUUCCCAGAACAUACCCUCAGAACCUGGGUCUUUUACCUAACUAUGGGGGCUACGUGCCAGGGUAUAAGUUCCAGUUUGGCCACACAUUUGGCCAUCUCACCCAUGAUGCUCUGGGCCUCAGCACCUUCCAGAAGCAGCUCUUGGCUUAGGCCACUGGACAUCAAGUUCCCUUCCCUUUUCAUCCUAUCCCAGCCAUCCUUUUGGAAGGGAGAGAGGUGGGUGGGAGGGUGGGAGGGUGGGGGAACACAAAGAGAAAAUGGUUUGGAGGCUGAGCACCUUUUUUAUUAAUAGGUAUAAUAAAUAAAUAAAUAAAUACAUAAACAGA